AGUCCCUGUAGUCUCCUGCGGCCGCGGCCUCUCAGCCAUGGGCGCCGUCUGGUCCGCCCUGCUGGUUGGAGGGGGUCUGGCCGGAGCACUUUUCGUUUGGCUGCUGCGGGGCGGCCCUGGCGACACCGGGAAGGACGGGGAUGCGGAGCAGGAGAAAGACGCCCCUCUUGGGGGAGCUGCGAUUCCGGGAGGCCAUCAGAGUGGCAGCAGCGGACUGAGCCCUGGACCUUCCGGGCAGGAGCUGGUCACCAAACCAGAGCAUCUUCAAGAAAGCAAUGGACAUUUGAUUUCUAAGACCAAAGACCUUGGUAAACUGCAAGCAGCAUCAUGGAGAUUGCAGAAUCCUUCCAGGGAAGUCUGUGACAAUUCAAGAGAACAUGUUCCUUCUGGACAGUUUCCAGACACAGAAGCUCCAGCUACCUCUGAGACCAGUAACUCUAGGAGUUACUCUGAAGUUUCAAGAAAUGAAAGCCUUGAAUCUCCUAUGGGAGAAUGGGGAUUCCAAAAAGGACAAGAGAUAUCUGCUAAAGCAGCUACAUGUUUUGCAGAGAAGUUGCCUUCUAGCAACCUGCUCAAGAACAGAGCUAAAGAAGAAAUGAGCCUCUCUGAUUUGAACAGUCAGGACCGGGUUGACCACGAGGAGUGGGAAAUGGUGCCUAGGCACUCAUCUUGGGGGGAUGUUGGUGUGGGUGGCAGUCUUAAGGCUCCAGUGUUAAACCUAAACCAGGGAAUGGACAAUGGAAGAAGCACUUUGGUGGAAGCAAGAGGUCAGCAAGUGCAUGGGAAAAUGGAAAGGGUAGCAGUGAUGCCUGCAGGGUCUCAGCAAGUUAGUGUCAGGUUCCAGGUCCAUUAUGUCACAAGCACUGAUGUGCAAUUCAUUGCAGUAACUGGAGACCAUGAGUGUCUUGGGAGAUGGAACACUUACAUCCCACUCCACUAUAACAAGGAUGGGUUCUGGUCUCAUUCCAUUUUCCUGCCUGCAGAUACAGUGGUGGAGUGGAAGUUUGUGUUGGUAGAGAAUGGGGGAGUUACCCGCUGGGAAGAAUGCAGCAAUAGAUUCCUAGAAACUGGCCAUGAGGAUAAAGUGGUUCACGCAUGGUGGGGGAUUCACUGAUUCAGUUUGCAAAGUAAUGGAGAAGCUGUAGAACAAUGUGGAAGAGGCUGAGGUUGUGGAACACACUGAAUAAAAUAAAGGCAGUGUGACUCCAAAUUCAGCCAUCUGAAUUGUUUAAAUUUGCUAGUGGAUUUUGUCUAAUGUGCAGAAAUAUAUAUGUCUAAUGUGCAGAAAUAUAUAUGUGUGUAUGUGUGUAUAUAUAUGCACACACACACAGAUAAUGCUUCCAGUGAAUGUGAACUUCUUUUCCCUGUGGCACUGAUUGACAGACUUGUGCUGAUCCAUUAUUACUUUAGGGCUUGAUUCUCUUGGGGAGUGACUUGGCUAAGCUUCAGGUGUAAACUGUGGUCACGGAGCAAAAACAUUAACCAGCUGCCCAGGGUUCAAGCUUGAGCCUUUAGGUGAUCUUUAAACUAUGGUAGUAAAAUAAGCCUCACUCAAACAUAGCUGACUUCCUAUUGGUACAGCUUGAAAAGCACUUUUUACUACAUACACAUUUUAUGCUUAAAAAGUUAACAUGAUACGAAACUGUGAUUAGAAAAUAUCUGGUCUGGAUGUGAUUAGUAAGGAUACAAGAUAAUGUUCUAAGACUGCCUAAUGCUUUUUGUUUGAUUUUCAUCUGCCAGGCGUUGUUAUGUGCUAUGAGGGUAGCAAGUACGUCUUUGUCUUAAUGAUCUAAGGCUGGUGUAGAAACAAAGGGCCUAAUGAGAACCAAUCAUCAUGGAAGUCAGUUGCGGGGGCAGCCCAUAAGGAAAGGGAAAGUGAGUGGGGUUGGGCAUAGGCUGAGUGAGGUGGCCUGAAUGACACCUCUUAGAGGACUGUGAAGUACAGGCACAGCCCGACUGCAGGGAGGGAUGCACCCAUCAUUUACCCAUGGGAGCAUCUGUAGGACCAUCUCUCUCCCACUUCUUCUCCCCUCCCCCACCGCAUCUGGCCAGAUGGACUGUCCUACAGCAAUCGUUUCCAUCUGUCACCCUCUUCCCUCUCCUUUCAUACCAGUCACUAUCUUGGGUAACAAAUUUAUACAGGACAGUGGUACAGAAAUACAUCUUUGCUCUGAGAAUACAGCAAAUAUUAACUUAAAUUAUUAUAACUGAACAAAUAAUAAAACCUGAAUUUUAAUAUCUUCA